ACGCGCGCAGGGAGAGCGCGAGGCGGCCUCUUCCUCCCCCCCUUCCUCCUCCGGCCCGGCCCAGACCGGUUCCAACCUGCUGGGGCCGGUCCCAACUGCCUCCAACUGCCACCAACCUCUGGUCGGGCUGUGGGGCGGGAAACUCGGUCCCGGCCGCCGAGUGGGGAAGGCGGGAGCUCGGGAUGCAGAGUGCACUCUCCCUAGGCCAGGCCUUCGAGGCCUAACUGUUCCUCAGACCAUAAAACCACAGUAGUAGGCUCCUUUGGGGCAGUGAGAAGUCCAAGACACAACCAAGAGGAGUUCCGUGGGGUCCAGCCCCAGAACCCACCUAUGAAUGAUGAUUAACGUGAAGUCCUGUCAGGAGAUUCCGUGCAGUUUGCGCAGGAAGCCUUUUGUGUCCCUAAGGCUCGUAGGUUGUCCACGAGGGCCACACUUGCUUGAAUUCACAGUCGACGUAGAUAAACAUGCAAAGAUGGAAACGUGUCCGUGCGUGCCCAUGACCGUUUCCCUCGCGGGCUGUGCGGAGCCUGAGUCUGGGAGCCCGAAGGUGAUGGGUUCCAAGUAUGUCUGCAGGCUCAGCAGAAAUGUAGCAUUAGAGGGAGCCCCAAAUACUGACACUACAGGAGUCCAGCAGGAUGGGAAAACCUCUUCCUGGAAGUCUUGCAUCUGUGUGCUUUUAGGUCGCUGUCUUCAUUUCCUUCAAGCCACGUUAAGCAUUCCCUAGAGUUAGGUGAUGUGGGAGAAAGAUGAAUAAGGGGCGGUUUCUCCUGUUAAGCAAAAUGUUGCUUUCCAUUUUCCCUGAUGCUCUGUGAAUGCCUCUCAUCCCCAUGGGCUCCUGAGUGAUGUGCAUGUUUAAAAGGAUCCCCAGCUGCGAGAGGUUUUGGAACCUGGGGGGUUGAACAGCUCUUAAGUUGUUCAGUGAACGAAGAACAGAAUCAUCUGUUGGAGUAGAAAGAACUCAAACCAGUCAGGAGGAACUCUUGUUAUAGAAGACCUUGGGAAACUGUUCUGGGGUUGGGGAACAUUGGUUAUAGGAAGUGUAUGGUUUCUUUGUGGGAUUCUUUGUUGUUGGCUGAAAUCAUUUAAGCUUCUUGACUACAGUCUGACUCACGUUAACCAUUCCUUUUCUGAUAUGGACAUUGCUUUCCUGGUCCUUUCUUACUGGAGAUCUUUCGCAGUCUUUCCAUUGAUUUUGGUGAGAUGUUCUUAGCUCAAAGACUACUGAUGAGUUGAAUGGUGUAGUCUUGAUUUUCGAAUCUGGAAACUUCACGUAAUUGGAACUUCUUUAUAAUCUCUGGUUGCUCAGAUCACUGUUUUUAGCAAAAUAAACACAUUUUGAGUCACGAGAGUCUUGGCUUCAGCAACUUGUGUUUCUGUGUUGUGUUGUCAUUGAGCAUACUAUGGAAUCUGUAAUAGAAAGGCUUUCUUAUUUUGGAAUUGACAGGUGAAACAAGUGAACAGCUGAUUAAAUGUCAGUAUCUGAGUCUUUGUCCUCUUGAUGCUCAUUUGUUUAAAACCUGUCUUUCCUGCCGGGCGUGGUAGCUCUCACGCCUGUAAUCACAGCAUUUUGGGAGGCCGAGGCGGAUCGCAUGAGGUCAGGAGUGAAGAGACCAGCCUGCCCAAUAUGGCAAAACCCCGUCUCUACUAAAAAUACAAAAAAUUAGCUGGGUGUGCUGGCGGGCGCCUGUAAUCCCAGCUACUCAGGAGGCUGAGGCAGGAGAAUCGCUUGAACCCGGGAGGCGGAGGUGGCAGUGAGCCGAGAUCGUGCCACUGCACUCCAGCCUGAGCGACAAGAGCAAAACUCCGUCUCAAAAAACAGAAACAAAAACAAAAAAAAAGCCUGCCUUUCCAUUCCUUGUGGCUAUGUUAGAUACUAAAGAAGGCUUCCCCACAACCCAUAUGCAUCUGCUUUGACUGGUGGUUUCUAUCAUCCUACAAAGACUGUGACUUAUUGGUGAGGGCAGCUGGACAACUCUGAGAGCAACUUAGAGAAAUCCAUCUUGGGCACACUCUAUAAAGGAGCUCCUUCUCUGCAAAUAGCACCCCAGAUAAGUGCACAAAAGCAAGAUACCCUCGUGGACCUACACGUCCUCCCGCUUUUCAACACCCUGAUGCCUGAAGUGUGUAGAAUUUGACAGCAGUAUCAAGAGCUGAGGAGAAGGAGAAGAUGGAAAGGAGUCUAGCAACUUAAAAAUCUCACAGCAUUCUCUGUGAGGUGACCUUUUUUCCUGUUGGUGGCUCAAUUUCUUUAGGACAUAAAGAAGAUACUGAGGCCUGUGACAGCCUGUGACAGUAUCAUCAAGUCGUAUCUGAACUUAUUGAACUGUUUCCUCCCCUUCCUUAUUCUUUAUUCACAGUUUGCUUUUCAUGUGCAUAAGUUGACUCAUUUGUUUCCUGUUAGCAUUUGAAACACCAUAUAGCCACCAUAAGUCCUGACAAAAUGACUUUUAAUAAGGAGGGGGAAGGUCCAUGUCCCACCUUCCUAUGAAAUUUUGGCCUAUUCACAAGUCUACCCCCACAUAAGAGAAGUAGUUAUGUUCUGUAAAGAAGAGGUUGAUAAAAACCUUUAGCAUGGUGUUUUGUGACUUAGAAGUUUUAAGUAGUCGUUCUUAUAUCUAAGCAUUUAUUAAUUUUGGUAAGAACAUUACUAUACGUUUCUGAUGUCACUUUUACUGUUAAGAGGUGCCAGGCAUCUGGUGACCUGUCACUUCAGGAUUUGUGUGAAUCAGACCAUCUAAAUAUAAUAUAAAUUAGAGACUGGUACUUGUAUUUCCUGAUUAAAAACAAAGUAACGUCUGUUUUACUAUUGAAGUAAGAGUACUUUAUAAUGAAUACAAAAAUGUAUAUUAAAUAUCCAGUAGAGCAUGCUAAAGUGAACAUUUCUGUUUUUAUUUCAGCAACUUAUUUUAUGGUAUUGUAGUUAUGGCCUGUCCGAAACUCUCUGACAUAUUCUAAACAGCUUUCAGAGAGUCACUGAGGCUUAUUUGCUACUACUGUUGUUUUUCCUUUAGCUCAGUUAAGAAAUGUUUAGUUAGCCGGGCAUGGUGGCUCACGCCUGUAAUCCCAGCAUUUUGGGAGGCUGAGGCGGGUGGAUUGCCUGAGGUCAGGAGCUCGAGACCAGCCUGGCCAACAUAGUGAAACCCCGUCUCUACUAAAAAUACAAAAAACUAGCUGGGUGUGGUGGCGGGCACCUGUAAUCCCAGCUACUAGGGAGGCUGAGGCAGGAGAAUCACUAGGACCCAGGAGGCGCAGGUUGCGGUGAGCCGAGAUCACGCCAUUGCACUCCAACCUGGGCAACAAGAGUGAAACUCCGUCUCAAAAAAAAAAAAAAAUGCUUAGUUAAUAGUCAGCAUGGUAGUUAAGAGUACUGACUCCAGGGUCACACCACCUGGGUUUGAGGCCCAGCUCUGUCAGUUACUAGCUGUGAGAUCUUGGGCAAGUGACUUACCUCUUUGUGUAUCAGUUUCCUGAGAAUAGGAAUAUUACCUGUCUCAUGGGGUUGUUAUAAGGGUGAAAUAAAUGAGUUCAUACAUGUAAAGCGCUUAAAACAGUGCUUGGCACUUAGCACAGCGUAGGUACUGUUCUCCGCCAUUAUUUGAACAGGGCCCUAGUCACUGCUUUCAGUUGCAUUGCUCCUUGCUUCAACAGCCCUGAUUGAAUGCCUUCUUUAGUUGCAUCCACACUAAAAUAGAUCCUUCAGUUCCUAGGGCACGCACGGGGCAGCAGCAUCUUCAGAGAACAGUUCUCUCUUCCACGUCCACUUGAAUUCUUAUUUCAUUCUCCAGUCUUUGUAGCGCCUCCAUCAUACUGCUUGUAUCUUACAUGAUGGAUGUGUGUUCUAAACUGACCCAUGCAGUUUAGGGCCAAAUACGUUGUUGUACAGAAAACAAUGUACAAAGAACAUGUUAGUUUAAACAUAUUACUAAAGGGUCAUAAAACUGGAGGUUUUCCAGGCUAGCUUUUUCAGGUUAGCUAUGUACAGAAAAACUUUGUGGGCUUUUUGUUGUUGUUGUUGUUGUUGUUGUUUUUGGUUUUUGAGACAGGGUCUCGCUCUGUUGUCCAGGCUGGAGUGCAGUGGUGUGAUCUCCGCUCACUGCAACCUCCGCCUCCCGGGUUCAAGUGAUUGUAGUGCCUCAGCCUCCUGAGUAGCUGAGAUUACAGGCACGCGCCACCACACCUGGCUAAUUUUUGUAUUUUUAGUAGAGACGGGGUUUCGCUAUGUUGGCCAGGCUGGUCUCAUACUCCUGACCUCGAGUGAUCUGCCCGUCUUGACCUCUCAAAAGUGCUGAGAUUACAGGUGUGAGCCACCAUGCCUGGCCAGAAAAACUUUGGAUAAAGUCAAGGUAUUAUAUAAUUUGGGGGAGGAUGAACGGGGGUUUGUAGUACUCUCGAAUAUUCUCUAACAUCAGUGACGUGAGUGACCCUUAUAUGAAUCUUCCUCAGUUUCACCAGCUCUAGGCCCCACAGGGCAAGGGGACAGUUAUAGAAAGAAGGGACCAUGGACACACAGGACUAAUUGCACACCCUUCCUGGCUCUUGUUAGUUCUUGGGGCCAGGACAGCUCACAGGUGUCAGAAAGUUCCAGUGAGCCCCAGUGAAAAGUGGGCUGAAAUAAUUGCCAGUGAUUGGCUCCCCCACUGUAAAACACUGACUUGCUUGAGUGCCCGUAGCACUUGAACUGUGGGUUGCUGUGUGUGUGUGCACGGGCGUGUGUGCCCAGGUGCGGUAGGGAGUUUCAUCGCAUCUAGGAGCUUCAUAGUAGCCAUAAGAUCAUAUUGUAUUUACUCUGACUAAAGGCCAGUGUGGGAUCAAAGACUCCCUUAAAGGUUCAGACACACUUACAAAUUCACCAGACACUUAUUUUAUUUGCCUGAAUAAUACUCCCUGAGCUUGCUUUUUCUGCCAGAGAGAAUAUUCUAAAUCAGGAUCACUUUAGAAGAUUUGGAAGCCACAUCUCUAUAGCUGUGUAGUGUGUCAGAUCCAUCCAAAUAUUUAAAGCUUUUUUUUUUUUUUUUGAGAUAUGGUCUUACUGUGUCACCCAGGCUAGAGUGCAGUGACGUAAUCAUAGCUCACUGCAGCCUUGAACUCCUGGGCUCAAAUGAUCCUCUCACUUCAGCCUCCUGAGUAGCUGGGACUGCAGGUGUUUACCACCAUACCCGACUAAUUUUUUAUUUUUAAAUUUGUUUUGUGAAGUCAGGUUCUUACUGUGUUGCCAGGCUGGUCUGGAACUUCUGGCCUCAAGCAGUCGUCCUGCCUCUGCUCCCCAAAGUGCUGGGCCUGAGACACCACACCCAGCCUAAACUAAAAGCCAUUUUUAGUAACUCCCACCAAUGUGGUUACUGUUACAAAGUUGUAUGGUUUCUGGGUCAUGUUUGGUAUCAGAAUGUGUAUGUAUAUCCUUAUAAAUAUGGAAUGUAGAACUGAUAAUAGUUUACCUAUCAGAUUUGCAAAAAUAAGGAAAGAUUUUUAGCAGCUUGUAACAAACAUAUACAUACUUGGAUAAAUAAUUUAGAAUUUUAACCCAUGGCUCAUAUGCUCUUACAAUAUUCUCUUUGAGGGUAAAACAUACUUUAUUCUUAAACUUAAAGAACCUUUGAUAAGCCGUGAAUUAUGAUCUCAGUGACUACAUUUCUUUUUAGGAGUUAUAUGUGGGGGAAGGAAAGAAGUAGCUAGCAGGGUUAACAUGGAAAGCAGGAGAUUAUAGACAAGCAUCAUUUGAGCCUUUGGAUACUACAAAUAAUCUUCAAAAAUGACAGGUUUUUUGGCUUUUUGUUUUUCCUUUCCUUUAGUGCUAGUUGCAGAAUCCUAUCAUAUUGUGGUUAGAUUUCAAUAAAGAAUGUUUAAGAUUAGGACUAUGUCUUGCUUUUUAAAAAGAUCCUAUAUUCAUGUUAAAGCUUGUAUAUAUUUGUUUUUUGUUUUUGUUUUUGUUUUUGAGAUGGAGUUUCACUCUGUCCCCCAGGCUGGAGUGCGGUGGCGCAAUCUCGGCUCACUACAACCUCUGCCUCCCAGGCUCAAGCAGUUGUCUGCCUCAGCCUCCCAAGCAGCUGGGACUACAGGCAUGUGCCACCAUACCCAGGUACCUGAAAGAAUUCCGCACAGAGCAGUGCCCACUCUUUGUGCAACACAAAUGCACGCAGCAUCGGCCCUACACCUGCUUCCACUGGCACUUCGUGAACCAGCGGCGCCGCCGGUCCAUCCGCCGUCGGGACGGCACCUUCAAUUACAGCCCUGACGUCUACUGCACCAAGUACGACGAGGCUACAGGCCUCUGCCCGGAGGGCGACGAGUGCCCAUUCCUGCACAGAACCACAGGGGACACUGAGCGCAGGUACCACCUUCGUUACUACAAAACUGGAAUCUGCAUCCACGAGACAGACUCGAAAGGCAACUGCACCAAAAACGGCCUGCACUGCGCUUUUGCCCACGGGCCCCAUGACCUCCGCUCCCCUGUCUACGACAUCAGGGAGCUUCAGGCCAUGGAGGCCUUGCAGAAUGGCCAGACCACGGUAGAGGGGAGCAUAGAGGGCCAGUCGGCUGGGGCUGCGAGCCAUGCCAUGAUAGAAAAGAUCCUCAGCGAGGAGCCUCGGUGGCAAGAGACUGCUUAUGUGCUGGGGAACUAUAAGACGGAGCCUUGCAAGAAGCCCCCGCGGCUGUGCCGCCAAGGCUAUGCCUGUCCCUACUACCACAACAGCAAGGACCGGCGGCGGAGCCCCCGGAAGCACAAAUACAGGUCGUCUCCAUGUCCAAACGUCAAGCACGGGGAUGAGUGGGGAGACCCUGGCAAGUGUGAGAACGGAGACGCCUGCCAGUACUGCCACACCCGCACCGAGCAGCAGUUCCACCCCGAGAUCUACAAGUCCACCAAGUGCAACGACAUGCAGCAGUCGGGCAGCUGUCCCCGAGGACCCUUCUGCGCCUUUGCCCACGUAGAACAGCCACCCCUGAGUGACGACCUGCAGCCUUCCUCAGCUGUGUCCAGCCCCACCCAGCCAGGUCCUGUCCUGUACAUGCCAUCUGCCGCCGGAGACUCGGUGCCUGUGAGCCCCUCCAGCCCGCAUGCCCCUGACCUCAGUGCCCUCCUCUGUAGAAACAGCAGCCUAGGCAGCCCGUCUAACCUCUGCGGCUCCCCACCGGGCUCCAUCAGGAAGCCCCCAAACCUGGAGGGCAUCGUCUUCCCUGGGGAGUCUGGCCUGGCCCCUGGCAGCUAUAAGAAGGCUCCCGGCUUCGAGAGGGAAGACCAGGUGGGAGCCGAGUACCUGAAAAAUUUCAAAUGCCAGGCCAAAUUAAAACCCCACUCAUUAGAGCCCAGGAGUCAAGAGCAGCCUCUGCUUCAGCCCAAACAGGACAUGCUGGGCAUCCUCCCCGCAGGCAGCCCCCUGACCUCAAGCAUCUCUUCUAGUAUCACCUCCAGCCUGGCAGCUACCCCCCCUAGCCCAGUGGGCACCAGCAGCGUCCCCGGCAUGAAUGCAAACGCUCUGCCCUUCUACCCCACCAGCGACACGGUAGAGUCAGUCAUAGAGUCUGCUUUGGAUGACCUGGACCUGAAUGAGUUUGGCGUGGCCGCCCUGGAGAAGACUUUCGAUAACAGCACAGUGCCCCACCCAGGAAGCAUCACCAUCGGCGGCAGCUUGCUGCAGAGCUCUGCACCCGUGAACAUCCCCGGCUCCUUGGGCAGCUCUGCCUCCUUCCACUCAGCAUCCCCGUCCCCUCCCGUCAGCCUCUCCUCGCAUUUCCUGCAGCAGCCCCAGGGCCACCUGAGUCAGUCGGAAAACACAUUUUUGGGAACCUCAGCAUCACAUGGAUCUUUGGGUCUGAACGGGAUGAACAGCAGCAUCUGGGAGCAUUUUGCCUCUGGAAGCUUCUCCCCGGGCACUUCCCCCGCUUUCCUAUCAGGGCCAGGGGCUGCCGAGCUGGCCCGACUUCGGCAAGAGCUGGAUGAAGCCAACAGCACCAUCAAGCAGUGGGAGGAGUCCUGGAAGCAGGCCAAGCAGGCUUGUGAUGCCUGGAAGAAAGAGGCGGAGGAGGCUGGUGAGCGGGCCAGUGCGGCGGGCGCCGAGUGCGAGCUGGCCCGGGAGCAGCGGGAUGCACUGGAGGUGCAGGUGAAGAAGCUCCAGGAGGAGCUGGAGCGGCUACACGCGGGGCCUGAGCCCCAGGCCCUGCCCGCCUUCUCCGACCUGGAGGCGCUCUCACUCUCCACCCUCUACUCCCUCCAGAAACAACUGCGGGCCCACCUGGAACAAGUGGACAAGGCCGUGUUCCACAUGCAGUCGGUGAAAUGCCUUAAGUGUCAGGAACAGAAGCGGGCAGUGCUGCCGUGCCAACACGCUGCGCUGUGUGAGCUCUGCGCUGAGGGCAGCGAGUGCCCCAUCUGCCAGCCUGGCCGGGCCCACACCCUCCAGUCGUGACCCUGCAGGCCUGGCCCAGCCUGGCCCAGAUCUUCUCACCUAGGACUUUUUAAAGUAUAUAUAUAUAUAUGAAUAUAUAUAUAUAUGUGUAUGUAUGUAUGUAUAUGUAUAUGAUUAUGUAUAUGUAUACAUUUCCGUAUGUAUGUAUAUGUAUACAUUUCCGUAUGUGUGCAGGUAUGCGUGGUGGUGUGGACAGUGUCUGUGUGUAUAUCUGUACAUAGAUAUAGACACACACUUUAAAAGACUUACCAAGCACUUUUUAAAAGAAGAAACUAUUUUGCAGUCCUCCCCUACCCACUCCCUGCCCUUCCCACUGCAGAGAUGACAUCCCCUCUUCUCCCACUGGCCUUUUGGCAGAGAAUCUGGUUCUGUCUCUUUUUUAAUGUAGGAACUAACUAUUUUUAACUUCUUCCUGGGGCCUGAGCAGGGAAGGGUGGGACUGGAAGGCACUAAGGGGAAGGGAGAAGCCCUCAGGGCAGGCCCUGCUCCCCCUACCUCCUUGCCAGGGCAAGGGUGGAGUGUGGAAGACGUGGGUCCCCCAGAGCAGGCCUGGCCCCCAGCUGUGAGGGCCUCAGGGAGGCCCGAGGGGGAGUGCUGGGGGUCUCAGCUGGCUUAGCUCCUAAGUUUACCAAAUGUUAAUUUAGUCUUGGGGAGAACAGCAAGGGCUGGAGGCCAGUGCUGCAGGGCCAGCCCCACUCCUGACACCUGGGCCCUUGAAGCUCCUUGAGGGGCAAGGCCCAGGAGUUCCAGCCCUCAGGUUCCUGAGGGUCCACCCUCAGUCCUUCCCCCCGCCGCCCCUCCCCGGACUCCCCACAAGAGCCUCCCUGGCCCCAGGGCCGCCUACCAGGCUGGUACUCAUUCUAUGACCACCGCCCCCAACCAGCUGCCCCCAGCUCUCCCUGCCCCCUCCCCUCUCUGGCAGCUAGCAGGGCAAUUGGCGGGGAGGAGUGCGGACUGAGGACUGAGGACCAAGGGGGCCCAGGCCCUGCCCUCCUACCCGGAGGGGCUCCGUUUGCAUUCCUUGGUGCUCUCUGAGUGCAGCUGGUGUCCCGCCCUGUUCUGGGCGGACGCCUGUGUGCGUGUGUGUGUGCCUGUCCAGUGUAUAUUGUGUCUUAGCUUCCAUUUUAAAAAUUGUUCUGUACAGAGAGAGAUGCAGCAGGGGCGGGAGGGCAGAGUGGGCGGAGGGGAGCAGCCGCACCCCCAGCACCGGGUGUCUGCGGUAGGAACAAGAGGGCUGAGAGGGUCUGGUCCUGGCCCAGGCUCCCCCUUGGGCUCAGCACGAAAGGGCUUUCAAUGAAUUAAGUGAAAACUUUUUCCUUUUUUACAAAAAUGCAAAAAUCAACAAAGCUCCAAACCUAUUGGAAAUAAAAUAUGAACUUGCA